GUUUGAUGCAGUCACCGGGGAAUUCACUGUAAGUAAGCUCCUUGUUUUGUUUUGUAAGCCACGAAAGAAUUCCUUUGUGAAAAUAGUUUUCAAGCAAGAAUUGCCAUGUCCCAAAAUGUCAGACUUAAUAUUUUUGAUGGUUCCAAAUAAGAUGGACAUUGCCUAGGCAAUCAUAGAUGGAAAUAGAGGAUGGCAACAGCAUUGACCAAAUUAUUUUGUCCAUCUUUUAAAAAAGUUUGAUCACUGUAUAGUCUCAACUUGGUUGAAAAUAUUAACUAACCAUGGCACAGAAGAUGUACUCCUGGCAGACAGAUACUGCCUGAGCUUUUUCUUUAUCAAGUGAAUGGAAUCAGAGAAUCAUCUACUCACCUUGGCCAGUGAAAAUAAUUCAUCUGAAUAAUUCAGGCUUUACAUUAAAACCUAGAAUACCCAGAUCAGCUAACUACGCUAACCAAGAAUCUCUAUGGAACUGACCUGUUUUUCCCUUUGAUUUCUAGAACAUAGAUAAGUUUUACAAUUUUUAGUAGGUAUAUUUUGUAGAUUUUCAAAAAACAAACCUUAUAUUUCAAGAAGAAAUAUUGAUGGAUAUAUCAUGUAUGUUCUAGUUGUUUUGGGCAUCUCUCUCCUCUCUCUCUAGAUAUCUCUCUCUAGAGAUGUCAUGCAAUCCAUAGUACAUACCAAUAAGAAUUCGCUGGACAGACCAUAGCUAUAGAUCAAGCCUUUUGCUGAAUAUUUGUAGUGCUCAAAUAGCACAAGAUCUCAGAUCUAUGGAAUUUUAUACUUUUCUUUUUUAAAAAAAAAGAACUGGUAUCUUUUUUAUUUUAUUUUAUUUUAGCUCAAGGAGAGAAAAGAUGUGGCUAUUGCUAGAAAUAUGUCCCCAGGAAGGUCAACUACCUUUUCCCAUACUAUUAGUGAACUCCAUCAAAAUGUACAUUCUGAAAUAAGGAGUAAUUUUGAGGGCAUUUCAAAAAAAAUCUUUGAUAGAGCCAUCACCAUCAAUUCUUGGGCUGUUAAACCAGAGAGAAAUUUACAUAUUAAGUAGUUGAGUUUUUUGUUUCAUAACAUAGUAGUGAAUAGACUGUGUUAUAUGAUUAAGCGGAAAAAAAGAAGGAACAAAUUAAUCUAUGUGGAGAAGCAAACAAUGUUGCUGAAUUGACAGUCAAAUUAUCUUAUUUCUUCAAUUCUGGAAGUAAGUGAUAGGAGAAUGGAAAUGGAAACAGUAAACACCUUGGCCUCAUAAAGUGGUGUAAGCUGAUUAUUUCUGCGUUCUCAGUAGCAAGCAGAGGAGAACGUUAAGAAAUAUUGACACAUAAAGUGGAGAUAGGUAAGAUUUAACCAAUUUCAUCAUUAAAGUCAGAGACAUUACUCAAAUGGCUUUGAGUGUGAACCCAUUCUUUACUAUAUUUGCAGAAUAUUCUCUUAGCCACACUUAGAUACUCCAACCUUGCUAUUAUGACUACCACCACCAUCAUCACCACCAGAAAAAAACGUAAUUUGUAUAACCUGAAAAACGUUCUAUUUUUAAAAAAUUACAAAAAGAUUGUAACUAUUUUUGCUGACACUUGAAACAAGAAGAUCCCUUAAACUUUAUAAAAAUUUUGCCUAAUAACUCUUCCCUUUUUUAUUAAUUUUUCCAGCUUUGACAUUUUAAUGUUCUCUGUGCUUUUCCUCAUUUAAACUACUAUUGUGUUUUAUUGUUGUCAUUCACUAUUUUUCUUUUCUUUUUUCUUCCUUUUUGUUUUCUGAUGUGAAAAUUUUCUCAUCCAGUUAUCUCAUGUGAUAUUCUAGUUGCUCUCCAAUAUUUUAUUCUUUCCACUUUUCAAACUUACUUGUCAUCUUAUGAUACAGUAUAUCUCUAGCUCUUUCAUUUAUCAUUCUGGAUUCUGAAUGGAAAUGAAAGAAAGUAAAUCACCACCAUCUUGCUGACUGCAGCACCAGUCAUUUUCAAUUUGCUGUCAAUUAGAACCCAAAGAACCCAAAGUGAUGGACUAUCUUUCCAAUGAUGAAAAACAGUUGGAUACAACCAAACCAUAUGAAACAAAUACUCCUCUCCCUACUAAAAAUAUCCCCAAUUUGAAAUAAGAUAGCUGUUCGGAAGUAUUCCAUUGUUACGAAUCCAUUGAAUAUAUAGAAAGACAUAGGCUAAAUUUGGAAAAUGGAAGUACUUUAUUGUCAUCCUGAUGAUCUUUUGUAACUACUUGUUCAUACAUUAUUCUUAAAGAUGCCAAAUUCUGCCCUUUUUGGUACUUUUUUAACCUGUGAUUUACAUUUACUAUAUUAUUAUGUUUAUUAAAUGUAAACAUGCCAAAUUAUAAAAAGCUUUUAAGAAAGUCUUUUUAUUGGUAGGAUUUAGAAUUGGGUCCUAAUUGUCAUAGCACCACUAAUUUAUUGUGUGUUGGGAGGGGAUCAUAUUAAGUUUGAUUAUCGUGGUUGUUGAGGUUGAAUUUUGUGCAAUUUGCUGAACUAUCUAAUCCAGUUGUCUUACAAGGGCUUGUUAUUUUGAAUAUUUGGACACUGAUUUGCUGUGUUGCUUGGUGAUUACUCUUUGGCUAAUUGGCCCAUAUGACCUUGUAUACCUGGUCAUACACUUGGACCCUGAAGCUAAAAGUAGGUUGGGAGGUGAGAUUUUUGGUAUUCAAUGAUUAUAAGUCCUCAUCCUUUAUAUUGCCAUUUUUGUCCCAAAUACUUCAGAACUCCCCUUUCCAGACCUCUAGACCUGUGACGGUCGCUUCAAGUCAAUCAGAGGGAAAAAUGCCAGAUCUCUAUGGCUCACAGAUGUGCCCAGGGAAGCUCCCAGAGGGAAUUCCAGAGCAAUGGGCACGAUUACUCCAAACUUCCAACAUAACAAAAUUGGAACAGAAGAAGAACCCACAAGCUGUUCUAGAUGUUCUCAAAUUCUAUGAUUCCAAAGAAACAGUCAACAACCAGAAAUACAUGAGCUUUACAUCAGGAGAUAAAAGUGCACAUGGAUACAUAGCAGCCCAUCCUUCGAGUACAAAAACAGCAUCUGAGCCUCCAUUGGCCCCUCCUGUGUCUGAAGAAGAAGAUGAAGAGGAAGAAGAAGAAGAAGAUGAAAAUGAGCCACCACCAGUUAUCGCACCAAGACCAGAGCAUACAAAAUCAAUCUAUACUCGUUCUGUGGUUGAAUCCAUUGCUUCACCAGCAGUACCAAAUAAAGAGGUCACACCACCCUCUGCUGAAAAUGCCAAUUCCAGUACUUUGUACAGGAACACAGAUCGGCAAAGAAAAAAAUCCAAGAUGACAGAUGAGGAGAUCUUAGAGAAGCUAAGAAGCAUUGUGAGUGUUGGGGACCCAAAGAAAAAAUACACAAGAUUUGAAAAAAUUGGUCAAGGGGCAUCAGGUACUGUUUAUACAGCACUAGACAUUGCAACAGGACAAGAGGUGGCCAUAAAGCAGAUGAACCUUCAACAGCAACCCAAGAAGGAAUUAAUUAUUAAUGAAAUUCUGGUCAUGAGGGAAAAUAAGAACCCUAAUAUUGUUAAUUAUUUAGAUAGCUACUUGGUGGGUGAUGAACUAUGGGUAGUCAUGGAAUACUUGGCUGGUGGCUCUCUGACUGAUGUGGUCACAGAGACCUGUAUGGAUGAAGGACAGAUAGCAGCUGUCUGCAGAGAGUGCCUGCAAGCUUUGGAUUUCCUGCACUCAAACCAGGUGAUCCAUAGAGAUAUAAAGAGUGACAAUAUUCUUCUCGGGAUGGAUGGCUCUGUUAAAUUGACUGACUUUGGGUUCUGUGCCCAGAUCACUCCUGAGCAAAGUAAACGAAGCACUAUGGUGGGAACCCCAUAUUGGAUGGCACCUGAGGUGGUGACUCGAAAAGCUUAUGGUCCGAAAGUUGAUAUCUGGUCUCUUGGAAUUAUGGCAAUUGAAAUGGUGGAAGGUGAACCCCCUUACCUUAAUGAAAAUCCACUCAGGGCAUUGUAUCUGAUAGCCACUAAUGGAACUCCAGAGCUCCAGAAUCCUGAGAGACUGUCAGCUGUAUUCCGUGACUUUUUAAAUCGCUGUCUUGAGAUGGAUGUGGAUAGGCGAGGAUCUGCCAAGGAGCUUUUGCAGCAUCCAUUUUUAAAAUUAGCCAAGCCUCUCUCCAGCCUGACUCCUCUGAUUAUCGCUGCAAAGGAAGCAAUUAAGAACAGCAGCCGCUAAGACUGCAAGCCUUACACCUCACCAUCUCCCUCAUGAGUAAGACUGAAAUAAAACUCUGCUGCAGGAAAGAUGGAAGAAAAGACAGUCAAAUGGGGUGGGGGUUCUUUACCUUUCAAAUGAAUAGAAACUUCUUAUAAGCCUUUUUCCUACUCCCUCAGAUUAUGUAAUUUAUUUGUAAGCCUGAAUCGCAGCCCAAACAGGGCAGCAAUGUUGAAGUGACCAUAAAGUGGUCACUUCCACCGUGAAGCGAAAGAGCCAGUAGUGAAUCCCCUCAUUUUGUGCAUUCACUUUGAAGAAAAAGGUUUCUCAAAGAUGCACACUCCCUCUUCAUAGUGUUGUGUUUGUUUUUAAGUUAGAGAGUAGUCCCUCUUGCAUUCAAACCUCCUUCAAAACUCCUUACCCAAUGUGAUGUUUUUCACUUGCAUUGUCAUUAGAUGUCCAGAAAAAAAAAAGAUGUCAAAAUGUUUUUCUAAAAAAAGAAAGCAAAAAAAGCAAGGCAAAAAAAAAAAAAAAAACAAACAAAAACAAAAACAAAACAAAAACAAGCAAACAAAAAAUACCAGAGCAAGUACUGUGUGAACAUGUGGAAGUCCAUGCCCUAAUAGAGUUGCAAUUUUUUAUUCUUCUUCUAUAGUGGUGGCUUGGUUUGUGUACCUAUUUUUCUGCAUUUGUAUUGGAAAAGGUUUCUUUUAAGACAUUUUCCAAAAGUGGAGAGGAAUAUGUGUGUUCAGGAAGGGCUUUCAAAAAACUGUAUAUCUAAAUAAAGCUCAAACGGUGAAAUCCUGUCACAUUUUCACAAUGAUGCUUAAAAGAUAAUUGAGUAAACCAGGUUGUUAAUCUCCUUAAUACCUGAAAGAGGACACACUGAAACUGAAACUGUGACAUCCUGCUAGGUGAGUUCAGGUUCUGAACCUAGGAAAUCCUCAUAGGAGAAACCACAUUUAAACAAAGAUGGGACUUUCUCUGAGAGCCAAAACCAGAUAAAUGUAGAAUACUGAAAUCCUUGUUGGACAUUAAGUAAACAAAGAUAAUGAUACCUAAAUUAAUCCUCUCUUGUGCUUAUGAAACAUAUGCACUGUAAAAUAGGCAUACCAGGAGGAAAUAGAUACAUUAAUCAUCAUUUACUUAUGAUACAAAUUAUUUAUUUUGACAAUUUAUAACGUUUAAAAAAGUUUUUUAAAGAUCUAGAGAAAGGUGAUAUAGUAAACAUUCAACUCUGUAAGAAAUGGGAGGUCAGUGAAGGCUACAUCCCAAUCAAUAUUUGGCUCUAAGUACCUCUUCCCAUUUUUCCUAUGUAUCACCUAUUUCUGUUUCGGAAUAUGGUGUGUUCAUGCUUAGUUCUUUGGGCUUUUGAAUAUCAAAAGCAUAUUCAUAAAUGUCUUGAAAUUCUCUCCAGUGGAAAAUAAUUUUAACUUACAAUCAUAUCCCAAGAAAUGUCAGUCCGACAGAAUUCCUUAUAUGACUUGGGGAAAAUAACAAAAUUUGACUACUAUUUCACCAUAUAUCUAUUUAUUAAAAAAUUCAACAGUUGGCACUUCCUGAAUCUUCUGAGAGUAGAAAAAUAUCUGCGGAGUGUCUGUGUAGAAAAGGAUAUGCCUCUCUUUUGAGUGUAUUGACAAUUUUGUAAAUUACAGAAAGUUGUUUCUCUAAGCCUUUGAAAAACUAACAAUUUGUGUUAUAGAAGGCUUCUUAAUUUGCAGUAUAAAAGAAUCUAAACAGAACUUAUGUACAUUCAGCCAGAAGGGGAAAGAGAUCAGUUACAUAGGCCUCUCUCCUUCUUUGCCAAGGUACAUCCAUCCAUCUAACCAUCCAUAUAUCCACAUCUUAAAAUGAAAGCACUUUCUUUAGAGUUUCAGCAAACUAUAUAGUGUACGUGUUUAUGUUCAGGAGAUGACCCCACUGGUGUAUUUCCUAUUUUCCCUAUUGUUUUCUUUGACUGUAAAAGUUGGGAGAGGCUUGACCUCCUCCCCUUGAAAAUGUCCACAGUGGGAUAAAACAACAAAUGUGAAAAGAAAAUGAAACGGUAAUAUUAAUUUGAAGCAUACUAUGUUAUACUUUGCAAAAACGAAUCUGGGCCUGUAAUUUUUAAUGCCACACUGCUCUAAUGAGAGAGAGAGGCCUUAAUUUUGAUUUCAUUUAAAAAUAAGUACUUUAAAAAAUUUUUCACUCAUAGUGCCGGGAAAUUCAAUGAAAUCCUGGGAUGCAAAUAAAAAUCAGUACAUUAGUGACUGUGUCCUGCCAGUGGAGAGAGCCCAAUACCUGGUUAGGAAGCCCUAUUCAUUAGUUAGCAUCCCUUACAUGUUGAGAAGGCCUUUUUUUUGUUGUUAUUUUGGAGACCUUGGAGCAGUGACCCUUCAGAUCACUGUAGGCAGAGAAAUGGCUUCUCUCUUAUGCUUUCAGUUCAGCAUAUUAACAAUGAGGAGCCAGGUACUUCUUUACUACCACUUUGUACCAAGAUUUGAUAAUAAUAUAUCCCAGGAGGCAUUACUUUUAUAAAUUUGUAUUCAUGUAAAUUUUCAAAUGAGAACAGCUUCUAAAGCCCCUUCCCUGUAUUGGAGAGUUAUGUAUAUUUCUAAUAAGUAUUAGAAAGAAGCUGUUUCUCAUGCCACAGUGAUGCUGAAGGAUUCACAUUUGGUACAAUCGAGUAACUUGAACGCCAGAUUGUUAACAGUUUAUUCUCUUUCCCUGGAUUUUUAAGCUCAUCUUGACACAGGUGAGUCUAUCCAAAUCUUUGAUGUUGCUAGUGUGCCCUGAGAUAACGAGGGCACAUCUUUCAAUGUUGAUUCCAAAAUGUCCUGAGUUAGGAAUAGGGCAGUGGGAAAGUCAGGGAAGGGUGAGAAGCACAGUAGAGAUUAUUUAUUUAAAAAAGGAAAGAACGUUAAUGUUGUUAGCAAGGAUCCAGUGCGUUGUCAUAAUCCCAUGAGGAUUUUCAGAUGACACAAUCCCCUCAAAUCAGUCACCAUGUUGGGUAAUGACUUCGUUCUUGCUGAUCUCGUGUGUGUGUCAUUGUAAAUAUUUGUGUGUCCAUGUUCCAUUUUGGCUACUGGAUGGCCAAGCCAUGUAAGAAGAUUUAACUCAAGUAUUUAUUCUUUAUGUUAUUCAGAUUUCUUUCAGGCUUGUGAACUGCACCCCAAUGUUUGAGUUUAACCACCUGAUCCUUACAUCUAUCCCUCCCCGGUGAAGCACAUUCCAUUGCUAAAAGAAAAAGAAACACGAAAUUGCUUCCUGUUGUCUGUAUAACUGUUUUGAUAGUUUGAGAUAUUUGUCUAUAAAUGAUAUUUCUCAGCUCAAAGAUCGUGUAAAUAAUUAUAUUCCUUUGCUCAAUGGGUUUAUUUCUAAUGAGGCUGCCAGUUCUGAGAGAUUCUAUAAUAUCACUUUUAAAUAACAUAAACAGGGAUUACAACUAUGUAAAAAGAAAUGCAUAUGGACAAAGACUGGGAACACAGAUAAUUGAAAUCAGUUGUGUUAGGGUGGUGGAAUUAUGUGAAUUUUUUUUUCUUUUUAAAAUUUUAUUUGAUAUUGUUAUAAUAUUGCUUUACAAUAAAUAAACAGCAGAAAGGGAACUAUAGACACAUAGAAAAGAUGCCAGAAGCAGAUGCCUUCUGGCCAGAGCGCAGAGCAUGCAGGGCAGAGAUAUUUGCUAGUUACAAUUAUUCCAUAGGCUUUAUGCUUGCCUGGGUGCUGAGGUUGGCACACGCUCGGGUAUGGCACACGCUUUCUUAGGAGACUAUUAUCUAUAAGUUAAAGCUAGGGAGAUGUCACUAUUAGAACUCCAAACACACUCUUCUGCUUUAAAACAGGUUGUCUGCCCUCUGCUUUGGUAUGGCAUUCGGGUGUCUGUUUUGUGGUUGCUUUAGAUUGGAGGGGUGACCAUUUUAUUAGCCCCCUUGAUAACAUCUGUUGCAGAUAUUGCCUUUCUGGAACGUUUUAACAGACUCUCAGGUUGAAUUUUGGAGGACUAGAAGGAUAAAAUCCCCAGCUCCCACCAUUUUCUUGUCCAACAGGAUAUUACUGUAUAUCAUUCAGGUAGGAUUCUUCUUUUAAUAACCAAUAGGGCAAGUCCCACUAAUUUCAAUAGAAGUUAUGACUUGCAAUUAAAAGCUGACUUUGAAAUCAUUAAACAAAUAUGUAGGACUGUCUCUGCCUGUUGGCAUUCAGUUAUAGUUCUGUUAAUUUUGGCUUGGGAUGGUCUCCAUGUGCUUUUUUCUGCCUAUUUAUAGGUUGUUUGCAGUAGUUGUGAUUUUUAAAGAGCAAGGGAGACCAUCUAACCAAAGGAUAACUUCCUUCUAACUCACCAAAGAAAUUUUAGGUGAGAACUUUAAUAAUGAGGUAGUCACCUCAGAUAUGCUGCUUAGUUUCACUAAAAGCAGACCCUAUACCUAGAGAAGUCACUGGCUUUUUAUUGGUCAUUCUCAAUACAGAAAUACUUAGGGGAGUCUUAACCCUGCCAUCCCCGGUUGAAUCUCUUGGUCUUUAUCUAAGCUACUUGCAGUUAAUAUUCAGUUAAGCAAAGGUAUGGCCAGUAGUGCAAGUAUCUCCCAGUCUCUGAGCUCUGAACAAGAGGACUGAAAUUCAGCAUUUGUAAACUGACAGUUUGAUGGGCCUGGGAUUUGAAGUGAACUCAGCACACAAUUCUGAACGUGUAUUUGCAUGUGGACUGGGAAGGAAAUAAAUGGGAACUUGGAAAUAAUGGAAUAUUUCUCCUAUGAAAGAAUUUUUCGUAGAAGAUUUGUUUUUGAUAUAAUCUUUCUGUUGGUUAGCUUUUAGUGUUUUCAUUCCUUUUCUGAUCCACACUCCUUUAAGUGACCAAAUGAAUAUAACCCAACAUGCAUUGGGAAUGUGUUUAAUAUUAAACAAUGUCUAACUGAAUCUGCAAAUGCGGGAACUGAGAUAUCACCUCCAUGUGCACACCUGUGUGUACGAGUAUUCUAUACAACUUGUAGCAUUUACUGCCACUUAAUUGGGUUGAACUUGCAAGAUAAACUUUUGGAAACUGCUUAGUGCCAUCGGAGUCUCCUUUAGAAGCUGCCAUCAGGCAAAUGCUAUCCCAUAAUACCAGCAGUAAGCCUGGCAACAUGUUCAACAGAUUUAGUACCCAAGAGGAAAUCAACAGCGAUAGUAGAGAAUGAGUCAGAUGUAGUGGGAUAAAUACUAGCCUAGGAAGAAGGAGCCCCGGAGUCUAAUAUGAGCUUUAUUACUAAAUUGCUAUGUGACGCUAGGCAAGUCACUUAACCUCUCCAUGGCUGUUUCCUCAUCUGUAAAAUAAGUGUAUUGGACUAGAUGAUCCUUAGGGUCUUUCCAAAAGUCUAACAUUCUAUGGCAUUAUAGGUUGCCUUGCAAAUUCAGCCUGCUAUAGUGAUGGCAAAUAUCACGUUUAAGCCUGAGUCUCUUAUGUUGCAGUUAAAUAAAAGAACUAUGUAAGAUGAUUUUUAAAAUUCAAGCAAAUGGGCCGGGUGCGGUGGCUCAUACCUGUAAUCCCAGCACUUUGGGAGGCCAAGGCAGGCGGAUCACCUGAGGUCAGGAGUUCGAGACCAGCCUGACCAACAUAGAGAAACCCCAUCUCUACUAAAAAUACAAAAUUAGCCGGGUGUGGUGGCGGGCGCCUGUAAUCCCAGCUACUUGGGAGGCUGAGGUGGGAGAAUCGCUUGAACCCAGGAGGCGGAGGUUGUGGUGAGCUGAGAUCAUGCCAUUGCACUCCAGCCUCGGCAACAAGAGUGAAACUUCGUCUCCAAAAAAAAAAACUCAAGCAAAUGAAGUUCAUAAUAAUAGGGGAUGUUGAUAAAACUUGUGGCAGCCUUCCAAUUCAUUUACAGUUGUUUCGUUUUGUUUUUGUUUUAAUGUCCAUUUUCUGUUGACUGUUCCCAGUUUUCAUUUUCCAUACAGUCUGUAUGUAAAGUCUGGUUUUCAUUAAGCUGUGGCCAGUAUUUGCCACUACAACAGAAACACACUGUCACACUUGCUAGAAUAUAACUGUACUUGAGCUUCUCCUUUCCUGUGAAGUAGUGCUGGGCUUUCUAGAGUUUAAUUCUCAAGUGGCACAAGAUAGCAGAGCCCAUGCAUUUUAAUGGCUGAGACUGCUAAGAGUGAACCUAAACACUUACAAGUUGCAGAGAGAAAUGAAAAAGUAAUUACAUGCUAUUAGCAUUGAGAAAUGUUGACAAAUUAAUUUGUUGGGAACCAAAGAUAGCAUUUCUGAUGACAACUCCCACAGUGAUUGGCCAGUUGUAUGAUGAGUACACUGCUGGAAAGAGGGUAAACUGGGAGUUAGUGGAUGGUCCCAAUGCCCUGCCUACAGCAGAGUGCCAACCAGCCCUGAGUGCAAAAUUCAAGUUCAAUGUGUGUGCUUGUGUGUGGUGUGCUUUAUGGACCCGCAAAUACCAUAUUCAUUAUUGAUGAUAAGAUCUUCACAGAAUCCUGUAGCUACUAAUGCAUUGAGUUUUUAAUCUCAGUACAUCAGCCAGGAGGAGCCAGAUCACAGGGUAGUGAUGUCUACUGGGAUUAUACUCAUAACAUCUACACAAAACAAGUUGAGAAGGAUCCACGUUUUCAUUGUUUAUCAGAAUUGUAUCUCAUUUGGCUGAGCAUUACUUUUGUCAGAAUGUGUUAUCUGUAAACCAUGUGUAGUGAAAUUCUUCUGUAACUUUGGAUUAAAGGUAUUUAUGGUCUUUUUGUUUGUUUGAUUUUUAAGUAAGUUAUUUCUUUUGUAGACCUGCUGAUGGUAUGGUUCCAUCCUUCUGACCUCAGCAUCCAAUCUUUUUAAGGAUUUUUGUUUUCAAUAUUGUUAUUUUAAAUUGUGGUUGAAGCAAUAGAAAAUUGAAAUAUGGAUUGUGCAUGACUGUGUCUUGAGUGUAAAAAUAUUGCAGUUUGAAACUUGGACCUAAAGUAUUGCAAAUAAAAAUGACAAACAUCAAUGA